ACAGUCCUCCAGCUUCGGAUCCACAGACGGAAUCAGGAGCAGACAACCGGAGCCCCCCCACACCUCCGCCCUCAGAUCCAGUUCAGGCGCCCAUCUCCCAGCAAUCAAGUCUUGCUCCCUGGCCUGCCCUCCGGCACCCUGGAGCCCCGCUUUCCACACAGCCUUGCUCCUCCCGGCCUGGCUUGCUGCCUGCAGGCCUCUCAGGGUCCUUCACCGUCUCUCCAGUCUCGGAUCCGGACCCGUGGAUCUCAGCCUCAGACCCUCCUCUGGCCCCGGCCUUGCCCUCGGGCACGGCCCCUUUCCUCUUCAGCCCUGGGGUCCUGCUCCCCGAGCCAGAAUAUUGUCCUCCUUGGAGGUCCCCAAAGAAGGAGUCUCCCAAGAUCUCCCAACGUUGGAGGGAGUCCAAGCCCAGGGGGAACUUGACAUACCACCAGUACAUGCCCCCAGAGCCGAGACAGGGAUCCAGGGCGGACCCCCAAGCCGAGGGGUCCGCCCUGGGUCCUCCUGGGCCAUCUCUGUGGGAAGGGACAGACUCGCAGCAGCCACAUCCUAGGAUGAAGCCCUCUCCCCUCACUCCCUGCCCACCAGGAGUCCCUAGCCCCUCGCCCCCCCCACACAAGUUGGAACUUCAGACCCUUAAACUGGAGGAGCUGACGGUCUCAGAGCUCCGGCAGCAGCUGCGCCUGCGGGGCCUCCCAGUGUCGGGGACCAAGUCUAUGCUCCUGGAGCGCAUGCGCGGCGGCGCGCCGCCCCGCGAGCGGCCGAAGCCGCGGCGCGAGGACAGUCCCGCGGGUGCUCCCUGGCCGCGCCUCAAGCCCAAGGCCCUGGCAGCCGCCCGGCGUCAGGGCUCGGUCAAGCCCAGCGCAGCAUCUCACAGGCCACCUCUUCCACGUGCCGCGGAUACCCCGGGGACGGCUCCGGCUCCAACUCCCACUCCGGCUCCUGCUGCAGCUCCAGCCCUGACCCCUUCCUCAGGGCCGGGCUCAGCGGCUCUGACUCUGGAGGAGGAGCUGCAGGAAGCGAUCCGGAGGGCGCAGACGGAGUCUCGCGCUACUGGCAGGCUGGAGUGCAGUGGCACAAUCUCGGCUCACUGCAACCUCCACCUCCCGGAUUCAAGCAGUUCUCCUGCCUCAGCCUCCCGAGUAGCUGGGACUACAGGUGCGUGCCACCACAGCAGCUAAUUUUUGUAUUUUUAGUAGAGGCAGGGUUUCACCAUGUUGGCCAGGAUGGUCUUGAUCUCUUGACUUUGUGAUCCACCUGCCUCGGCCUCCCAAAGUGCUGGGAUUACAGGCGUGAGCCACCACGCCUGGCCUGUAUCUUUUCGAUUUUUAAAAAUUUUGUUAGUGAUGGUGUCUUGCUAUGUUGCGACUUUGGAAUGCAGUGGCUAUGCACAGGUGUGAUUGUGGCUCACUGAAGCCCCAAACUCCUGGGCUCAAUUGAUCCUCCCACUUCAGCCUUCCGAGUAGCUGGUCCUACAGUUGUAUUCCACUAUACCCAGUUAGUUUUUUAUUUUUUGUAGAGACAGGAUCUCCCUAUGUUGCCCAAGCUGGUCUUGAACUCUUGCUCUCAAGUGACCCUGCCACCUUGGCCUCCCAAAGUGUUGGGAUUACAGGCGUGAGCCACUGCACCUGGCCUGUACCAAUUAUAUUUUGAAGUGAUUUGUUAAUGCCGUCUUGAGAGCAGGGAUCGUAUCUCCUAGAUUGCUUUCUGAUACAUGAUAGGUGCACAGUAUGUAUUUGUGGGUAGUCUGGAGAAAAUACUGUAAUAUUGAGAUCUAAAAAAUCGUUGUAAAAGUUGCCUUGUUCUUUUUUUUGACCAAGUUUCGCUCUUGUUGCCCAGGCUGCAGUGCAAUGGUGUGAUCUCAGCUCACUGCAACCUCCAUCUCCCAGGUUCAAGCGAUUCUUCUGUCUCAGCCUCCCUAGCAGCUGGGAUUACAGGCAUGCACCACCACGCCUAGCUAAUUUUGUAUUUUUAGUAGAGACAGGGUUUCACUAUGUUGGCCAGGCUGGUCUUGAACUCCUAACCUCAAGUGAUCCAUCUGCCUCAGCUUCCCAAAGUGCUGGGAUUACAGGUGUGAGCCACUGCACCCAGCCAAAGCUGCCUUUUUGAUCCAGACUUGUAAUAGGAUUCCAUCUACUCUUAAGAAUUUUUUUUUUUUUUUUGAGAUGGAGUCUCACUCUGUUGUCCAGGCUAGAGUGCAAUGGUGUGAUCCUGGCUCACUGCAACCUCUGCCUCCCUGGUGCAAACGAUUCUCCUGCUUAAGCCUGCCAAGUAGCUGGGACUACAGGUCUGCACCACCACCCCUGGCUAAUGUUUUGUAUGUUUAGUAGAGACAGGGUUUCACUAUGUUGCCCAGGCUAGUCUCGAACUCCUGACCUCAGGUGAUCCGCCCGCCUUACCCUCCCAAAGUGCUGGGAUUACAGCCACCAUGCCUGGCCUAAGAUGUAUUUUGGAGUUCAUGUGAUACUUAUGUAAUACGCUCUCAGAGAACCUUUUCUCCCAUCCGCAAAGUCAUAAUUGUGUUUAUUCAUUUAUUUAUUUAUAAGAGUCAGGGUAUCACUACGUCGUCCAGGCCGCAGUGCAGUGGCUAUUCGCAAGUCCAAUCACGGUGCACUAUAUUCCCUAACUCCUGGCAUCAAGCAAUCCUCCCACCUCAGCCUCCCUGGUAGCUGGGAAUACCCAACUCCAUGACUGUAUGCACACUGGUGAUUAAAAAAAAUUAUUCCUUUGA